ACAGCCCGCUGGGCCGGAGGAGGCGGAGCUGGCGCUGUCCCGGCUCUCUUGCGGGGAAGCAACUGAGGGGGCGGCGCGGCGGGCCCCGGCGGCCGAAGAGGCUGGCAGGUGGCGCCGUGGGGUGGGUGCUCCUGGUGAGAGGAGUCCACUCCGUGCGUGCGGGCGGAGGCCGGCCCCCGAGAGCCGCCGACAUGAAGAAAGACGUGCGGAUCCUGCUGGUGGGAGAACCUAGAGUUGGGAAGACAUCACUGAUUAUGUCUCUGGUCAGUGAAGAAUUUCCAGAAGAGGUUCCUCCCCGGGCAGAAGAAAUCACCAUUCCAGCUGAUGUCACCCCAGAGAGAGUUCCAACACACAUUGUAGAUUACUCAGAAGCAGAACAGAGUGAUGAACAACUUCAUCAAGAAAUAUCUCAGGCUAAUGUCAUCUGUAUAGUGUAUGCCGUUAACAACAAGCAUUCUAUUGAUAAGGUAACAAGUCGAUGGAUUCCUCUCAUAAAUGAAAGAACAGACAAAGACAGCAGGCUGCCUUUAAUAUUGGUUGGGAACAAAUCUGAUCUGGUGGAAUAUAGUAGUAUGGAGACCAUCCUUCCUAUUAUGAACCAGUAUACAGAAAUAGAAACCUGUGUGGAGUGUUCAGCGAAAAACCUGAAGAACAUAUCAGAGCUCUUUUAUUACGCACAGAAAGCUGUUCUUCAUCCUACAGGGCCCCUGUACUGCCCAGAGGAGAAGGAGAUGAAACCAGCUUGUAUAAAAGCCCUUACUCGUAUAUUUAAAAUAUCUGAUCAAGAUAAUGAUGGUACUCUCAAUGAUGCUGAACUCAACUUCUUUCAGAGGAUUUGUUUCAACACUCCAUUAGCUCCUCAAGCUCUGGAGGAUGUCAAGAAUGUAGUCAGAAAACAUAUAAGUGAUGGUGUGGCUGACAGUGGGUUGACCCUGAAAGGUUUUCUCUUUUUACACACACUUUUUAUCCAGAGAGGGAGACACGAAACUACUUGGACUGUGCUUCGACGAUUUGGUUAUGAUGAUGACCUGGAUUUGACACCUGAAUAUUUGUUCCCCCUGCUGAAAAUACCUCCUGAUUGCACUACUGAAUUAAAUCAUCAUGCAUAUUUAUUUCUCCAAAGCACCUUUGACAAGCAUGAUUUGGAUAGAGACUGUGCUUUGUCACCUGAUGAGCUUAAAGAUUUAUUUAAAGUUUUCCCUUACAUACCUUGGGGGCCAGAUGUGAAUAACACAGUUUGUACCAAUGAAAGAGGCUGGAUAACCUACCAGGGAUUCCUUUCCCAGUGGACGCUCACGACUUAUUUAGAUGUACAGCGGUGCCUGGAAUAUUUGGGCUAUCUAGGCUAUUCAAUAUUGACUGAGCAAGAGUCUCAAGCUUCAGCUGUUACAGUGACAAGAGAUAAAAAGAUAGACCUGCAGAAAAAACAAACUCAAAGAAAUGUGUUCAGAUGUAAUGUAAUUGGAGUGAAAAACUGUGGGAAAAGUGGAGUUCUUCAGGCUCUUCUUGGAAGAAACUUAAUGAGGCAGAAGAAAAUUCGUGAAGAUCAUAAAUCCUACUAUGCGAUUAACACUGUUUAUGUAUAUGGACAAGAGAAAUACUUGUUGUUGCAUGAUAUCUCAGAAUCGGAAUUUCUAACUGAAGCUGAAAUCAUUUGUGAUGUUGUAUGCCUGGUAUAUGAUGUCAGCAAUCCCAAAUCCUUUGAAUACUGUGCCAGGAUUUUUAAGCAACACUUUAUGGACAGCAGAAUACCUUGCUUAAUCGUAGCUGCAAAGUCAGACCUGCAUGAAGUUAAACAAGAAUACAGUAUUUCACCUACUGAUUUCUGCAGGAAACACAAAAUGCCUCCACCACAAGCCUUCACUUGCAAUACUGCUGAUGCCCCCAGUAAGGAUAUCUUUGUUAAAUUGACAACAAUGGCCAUGUAUCCAGAGGAUCAUUACAGAGACAGACUCUCCCGAGACAUGGGCCACACUGAUAGAAUAGAGAAUUUGAGAAAAAUCUGGGUCUUUCUAAAAACUGCUUUCCAUGCCCGGUUACGCUGUAUGUGCACCUGCAACAGGUGUACAUUUUGCAUCUGUCAGAACUUCCUCAACUCAGACUUGCUGCAAUCUGUAAAGAACAAAAUCUUCACUGCAGUUCUUAACAGUUUUAGUUCUGCCCUUUAGAACAACAUACGACUAUCCUACUCCCUCUUCAACAUAGCAAUCCUUCAGGCAUUUGAAGACGGCCAUCAUGUCUCCCCUAAUUUUCUCUUCUCCAGGUAGAACAUCCCCAUUUCUUUCAGCCUUUUCUUAAAUUAGAUGGUUUAGUGAACUUAUCAUUCCUGGUUGUCUUCAUCUGAAAGCCCCUUAGGUUUUCACAGUACCUCUUAAAAGGUGCCACCAAGAAUAGAAAGCAGUGUUGCAGUUGUAGUGCGACUAGUCCAGAACAGUGGGCAGCUGUUUUUCACAAUUAGGACAGCAUCUGUCUAGGGCAUGAAUUAACUUUUUGGCAGUCCCAUCCCACUGUUGACAUAUAUUGUCUUGGGGCUAAUUAAAGUCAGAUGUUUUUCAUAUGAAGAGACAGAUGUCCCCUCCUUUCUGAUGUGUAUUUGACAUUUUUUAGUUGAUGCUUUAAAUCUAAAUGCAGAUACAUAUAUAUCUCUAUUAAAUGUCAUAUUCUUCUUUUUGAUCCAUUUGUUCUAGCUCAGUCAUUUCAAACAUUAUUUCUGUCAUUUGUCCCAUUAUAUAUUUCUCUAAGCAUUGUGUUAUUUGCAGAUUUGGUAGAUAUGUACUGUUUUUCAAGUUACUGAUAAAAAAUGAUGUUGAAUACCCAGAGGUUGGAGAGAGAGAGAGUGCUAAACUGAGCAAGCCCUAUAGUAUUCCACCAGAGAACUCUUUGUCAAUGACAGGUUCAAAAUUCUUGGGGAAGGAUUUUUCAGUCAAUGAAAAAUAUGUUAUUAUCCAGCCCACAUUUUGUCUUCCUGUCUUAUCAGAUAUUUCAUGAAGGAUUUUUCUAAAAUCAGUAUAUAAUUUCUUCCAUAUUCCUCUGAUCUACCAAUAUCAUAAUUUUAUCUAAUUAGCAAGCAACAUCUAUUUGAUGUCUUAUUUUGGUGAACUCACCUUGGCUCCCCGUAAUUGCUGAUCACAAACCACCUAUUUUAUUACCUAUUCUAGAAACUCUUGAUUGUCCAUAAUUACAGAUUGAUUCAUUGUCUGUGUCCCUGGUGACAAUUUUAUUCCUAGAUUGGUUUAGUUAGCUUUCAAAUAAAAUUGAUUUAGUUAGCUUUCAAAUGAAAUAGGACAGAUGUGCAUUAAAUGAAUACUAUUGUGCAUAGUAAAUUAUACAAUGGCCCUCAAAGAGAAAUCAGUACGUUUCGGUCAUAUCUAUUUAUAAACUGGUAGUAAUUUAAUGGUGAUGUCAGCACACAUCCUGACAUCUGGUAAUCAAGAAUGGAAAGAAUGAAAACGACAAGUAGAGGAACCAGUAUACUUUUCAAACACUCCUUCCUUAUCCCCGUUAGUAUUUCAAUCAUUUAUUUAAGAGAAGUACAGUGGAAUUUUAGGGGCUGCGUAUUGGAGUUUCUUCUAGUUUAUGAAAGGUAAGUAAGAUAGGUAGGUGGGGGCCAAAAACUCAGUGCCCACAGGUCCCGGAUGGAUACUGUAAAAGAAUGAAGGUGGCCAAGUAUAAGAAACAAGGAGAGGUGGGGACUGUGACAGGCACUGUCUAAAAGAGGCAGCCACCACUCAGCUCUGGCCGUUUGUUGUUGUACAGGUCUGGUGUUGCCAGGUUUUCUGGUUUUACAAGAGACUGGAAAUCAAGGCUUUGGUGUGAAAUUUCCAGAUUGUUAGAGAUUAGCAAUUAAUUAACAAAUUUUUAAGUACUAAUCAGAACAAAGCAUGUUUAUAGUCCACCAGCUUGCAACCUCAGUCUUAAGGUAUGGCCUAGUCAUGAAAAUAGAGGCCAAGGAAAAGGACACAUAGAAUGAAAAUGUCUCUGGUCCCAUCACCACCACCACCACUUUACUCCUUUCCCAUGAAAAAUUUGAAAAAGUUAUUGGGUGGUGGGAUGAGAAUGGAACCACCUUUCCCUGUUACUUCUCAGGUUUUGGCAGCUGUUACUGGUUGGUCACUAUUGGUUUCCUGUGUUAGACAUAUCCUAAUGUUAGGCACAAAAAAGAUUGAUUGACUAAGUAAAAGUCAUUUAAAAUUUUUUCACUGUAUUUUAUUCAUAGGGAGGGUUCUCACCUAACACUAGGUCCUAAGUCUUUGUUUUUAGAUAUCAGAACUACCAUGCUUAGUGUUUGAUUUAGAAUUGUGAAAGAGCAGUUCUAAAAGGCUUGUCUUUUUUUUUUUUUUUUUUUUUUUUUUUUUUGAGAUGGAGUCUCACCCUGCCACCCAGGCGGGAGUGCAGUGGCAUGAUCUCGGCUCACUGCAACCUCCACCUCCCAGGUUCAAGUGAUUCUCGUGCCUCAGCCUCCGGAGUAGCUGGGACCACAGGCAUGUGCCACUUUGCCCGGCUAAUUUUUGUAUUUUUAGUUUCGCCAUGUCUCAAACUGGUCUCGAACUCCUGACUUCAGGUGGUCUGCCAGCCUCAGCCUCCCAAAGUGCUGGGAUUACAGCUGUGAGCCACCGCACCCAGCUGUCAUUUUUAUUUAAGUAAAAAGUUUCAUUGAAUGUCUACAAAGAAUUAAAUUAGUAGACAAGUAUUGGUCUCAAAUCAGCACAUUGUUUUAGUGUGCUUGUAAAAAUUUUGGUCACUGAAAUAGAAAUUACUACCAGAUAUGAUACAUGUUUGAGACCACAUUCUCUUAUUACCCCACUGUCCCCUAACCCCACCUUGAUGUGAUUUAUUCAUUCAGAGUACUUAAUUUAAGUACCUGCUUUAAAUAGGAACCUGCUGUGAACUGGGGCAAAAUUUGAAAAUGAAGAAUAUAUGGAACCUGCCUUUAAGCAUCUUUCUAAAUAUUAUUUCUCUAAGAAAAACAUUUUUUAACUUUGGUUAUAUUUUCAGUGAUGUUAGUCCUUCAUGCUAAAAAGGAAAGUGCUAUAUAACCUGAUAAUGAAUUUAGGCAGUUUCAAGAGGUUAAUUUCUGCAAGUGUUUUUCCUUUUAUGAGAAAAAAAUUGUCUUUUUUCCUGAACUUAUUUACUAACACGAUAUAUUUUAAGUAUAGAAAGAAUGAAUUAAAAAUUUUUAUUUCCAAUUUAAUUGAACGUAUAUUAACUUUGAUGUGUGAGAGUAGUGUUAAACAUACAUCUAUCUCACAUGUAAUCUUUCUCUUGGUAAUUAUGAGCUCACUCAGAUCUGGAUAGGUUUAUGUUUUACUUUAGACUAAUUUAUGAAUAACUGGAAUUAUUUGAAUUUGAAUACAUGUGGAGGAUGAGUAACAUGUGGUCAGAUGAUUUUAAUCUUUGGGACUGCUUUCAUUUCAAGUGGUAUAAAUUACGUUACUGGAGAAAAAGACCUUUUGAAUAUAUUUUAAAUUUUAAAUAUCUUUUAAAUUUGAAAAUGAUUAUAUAUAGAUGAGCUUGAUUGUUGGUUUGAACUACCCAGGAUUUUUAUUUAUUAAGUAUUUAUUACUCUGACUUGAGAACACUCCUGCUUUGCAUGAGAAUGUUACUAGAUUGUAGUGUAUCGUGAACUUUAAUUUGUCCUUUUUUAGGUGUUUGUUUUCAUUUGUUUGUUUGUGUAACUUAGUCAUUUUUUGAUACUCUCAAUCUCCUUCCCAGCUAGGUUUUUGUGUAUAAUCUCACCACUUCUAACCUGUUAUUUAAUCAAAUAUUGCUUAUUUUACAGUUUAUUCUUUGGGCGUGAUUUCCUUUGUGCAUAUUUUGGUUUUAGGAUUUCUUUCAUUCUAUUUUAUUAUUUGCAUUAGCCAUAUAAGUUGUUGGUUCAUGUUACUUCUUAAGUUCAGUAGCAGCAUUUUAUUUUGACAACCAAGUGCAUAGUUCACACCGAAUAUUUACAGAGACCCAAAAGUAUGAUGGAUAGACAUCAUACCUAUUGCAUUUUUUACCCUAUUUAUAAUGUAUUUUUAGAUUAAAUAUAUGUGUGACUUUUAAGCCACUCAUUAAUGACUUCAUUUACCCAUAUUGCUUUAAUAAUCACCCAAGUUCUUCCUUUAUGUAGUUUGAAUUCAUUACUUAAUAUAGGAGCCCUUUAUUGAAGAAAGGAUUUUAUUAUUGUCAGACAAAAAUGAACUGCUUUUUCAUAGGAUUGCCUUAUGAAAAGGAUAGGUUUCUAAAAAUCUUAAUGUUGUUAAAUGUUGGAAAUCUAAGAGUCUUUGGGAUAUUACGUUAUAGUAAAAUAUUUUGUCCAAGGAAGUCCUGCUUUAGUUUCUUAUGAAACUUAUUUAUUCCCUUGUAUGAAGGUCCUUAUAAGACUGUUUGUGAAUUUGUAUACAUAGUCAUAUAUUUAAAGUUAUACAAGAGUUUAUGUUAUAGAUUUUCAUUAAGUAAGCUGCUGCUGCUUAUAAUUUUUAAAUUUUUUGUCAUUUGGUUAAUAUAUUAAAGGACAUGACAAGGUGAAGUUUGCCUUAUCUGAUCUUUAAGUAUCACUAGUUAACAUAUAGAUAUUGGAGCAUUUCCUUUGUAUUCAUGAUCAUCUGUAAAUUCAGAUUCUUCUAAUGCUUGGUGAAGCAUUUCUUGACAUUAGUGCACACCUGUGUCGUUUCCCAAAGUAUGUUACUAUUUAGGCGUGCUCAGUUAACAGCUUGCUUAUGGUUUGUGUUGAAGCUGCUAGACACUGUGUAUUGAUUCCUUAACCUAUUUUAUCCUAUUAAAUAUUUAUCCUAAUAUAUGUUUAUCCUAAUAAAUAUCCUAUUAAAAUA